ACGGAAUCCCAGAGGGCUCCGCCCAGCGCUACGGGGCCCCGCCCCGCCGCCUCUCAACCAUCAGGUUCGGCAGCCCGCGGCGCCGCCUGGCAGCUCCUCCUCUUCUCCGCCCCGCCGGCCGCGGGCGCGGGGGACGUCAGCGCUGCCAGCGUGGAAGGAGCUGCGGGGCGCGGGAGGAGGAAGUAGAGCCCGGGACCGCCAGGCCACCACCGGCCGCCUCAGCCAUGGACGCGUCCCUGGAGAAGGUCCGUGCCGGGAGGGGGCGAUGGGGACGGUGCUGCGGCCCGGGGCUCCCGCUUCCGAGGCAACUGUUUCCCAGUCGCGAGCUGCCAUUGUGACCCGGACAGGGGGACGCGGGCUGACAGGCCCUGCCUGAGGAGGCCUCGCCGGGAGGGCGGCUGGGGCCCGGGCGCGUCACGGGGCCGGGUGUCUCUUGGGUCCCCGUGGGCCGAAGAGGCUGGGCGGGGUUCGGUGGGGGCCGCGACGGGCCCGGAGCCCAGGACUGGGACCGCGGGGCCGACCUUGGGCCCUGCCGAGGUUCCGCGAGUGGCCGGCCUGAGCUCGGCUGGCCCUUUCGGAGGACCGGGAGCUCUCCGUUGGCGGCCCCAGAUGCUCCCGGAAAGAAGCCGCAGUUAUUUCAGAGCCAGCUGCAAACCUAUAGCAGACCCCACGUUAGCUGAAAUGGGAAAAAACUUGAAGGAGGCAGUGAAGAUGCUGGAGGACAGUCAGAGAAGAACAGAAGAGGAAAAUGGAAAGAAGCUCAUAUCCGGAGAUAUUCCAGGCCCACUCCAGGGCAGUGGGCAAGAUAUGGUGAGCAUCCUCCAGUUAGUUCAGAAUCUCAUGCAUGGAGAUGAAGAUGAGGAGCCCCAGAGCCCCAGAAUCCAAAAUAUUGGAGAACAAGGUCAUAUGGCUUUGUUGGGACAUAGUCUGGGAGCUUAUAUUUCAACUCUGGACAAAGAGAAGCUGAGAAAACUUACAACUAGGAUACUUUCAGAUACCACCUUAUGGCUAUGCAGAAUUUUCAGAUAUGAAAAUGGGUGUGCUUAUUUCCACGAAGAGGAAAGAGAAGGACUUGCAAAGAUAUGUAGGCUUGCCAUUCAUUCUCGAUAUGAAGACUUCGUAGUGGAUGGCUUCAAUGUGUUAUAUAACAAGAAGCCUGUCAUAUAUCUUAGUGCUGCUGCUAGACCUGGCCUGGGCCAAUACCUUUGUAAUCAGCUCGGCUUGCCCUUCCCCUGCUUGUGCCGUGUACCCUGUAACACUGUGUUUGGAUCCCAGCAUCAGAUGGAUGUUGCCUUCCUGGAGAAACUGAUUAAAGAUGAUAUAGAGCGAGGAAGACUGCCCCUGUUGCUUGUCGCAAAUGCAGGAACGGCAGCAGUAGGACACACAGACAAGAUUGGGAGAUUGAAAGAACUCUGUGAGCAGUAUGGCAUAUGGCUUCAUGUGGAGGGUGUGAAUCUGGCAACAUUGGCUCUGGGUUAUGUCUCCUCAUCAGUGCUGGCUGCAGCCAAAUGUGAUAGCAUGACGAUGACUCCUGGCCCGUGGCUGGGUUUGCCAGCUGUUCCUGCGGUGACACUGUAUAAACACGAUGACCCUGCCUUGACUUUAGUUGCUGGUCUUACAUCAAAUAAGCCCACAGACAAACUCCGUGCCCUGCCUCUGUGGUUAUCUUUACAAUACUUGGGACUUGAUGGGUUUGUGGAGAGGAUCAAGCAUGCCUGUCAACUGAGUCAACGGUUGCAGGAAAGUUUGAAGAAAGUGAAUUACAUCAAAAUCUUGGUGGAAGAUGAGCUCAGCUCCCCAGUGGUGGUGUUCAGAUUUUUCCAGGAAUUACCAGGCUCAGAUCCGGUGUUUAAAGCCGUCCCAGUGCCCAACAUGACACCUUCAGGAGUCGGCCGGGAGAGGCACUCGUGUGACGCGCUGAAUCGCUGGCUGGGAGAACAGCUGAAGCAGCUGGUGCCUGCAAGCGGCCUCACAGUCAUGGAUCUGGAAGCUGAGGGCACGUGUUUGCGGUUCAGCCCUUUGAUGACCGCAGCAGUUUUAGGAACUCGGGGAGAGGAUGUGGAUCAGCUCGUAGCCUGCAUAGAAAGCAAACUGCCAGUGCUGUGCUGUACGCUCCAGUUGCGUGAAGAGUUCAAGCAGGAAGUGGAAGCAACAGCAGGUCUCCUAUAUGUUGAUGACCCUAACUGGUCUGGAAUAGGGGUUGUCAGGUAUGAACAUGCUAAUGAUGAUAAGAGCAGUUUGAAAUCAGAUCCCGAAGGGGAAAACAUCCAUGCUGGACUCCUGAAGAAGUUAAAUGAACUGGAAUCUGACCUAACCUUUAAAAUAGGCCCUGAGUAUAAGAGCAUGAAGAGCUGCCUUUAUGUCGGCAUGGCGAGCGACAACGUCGAUGCUGCUGAGCUCGUGGAGACCAUUGCGGCCACAGCCCGGGAGAUAGAGGAGAACUCGAGGCUUCUGGAAAACAUGACAGAAGUGGUUCGGAAAGGCAUUCAGGAAGCUCAAGUGGAGCUGCAGAAGGCAAGUGAAGAACGGCUUCUGGAAGAGGGGGUGUUGCGGCAGAUCCCUGUAGUGGGCUCCGUGCUGAAUUGGUUUUCUCCGGUCCAGGCUUUACAGAAGGGAAGAACUUUUAACUUGACAGCAGGCUCUCUGGAGUCCACAGAACCCAUAUAUGUCUACAAAGCACAAGGUGCAGGAGUCACGCUGCCUCCAACGCCCUCGGGCAGUCGCACCAAGCAGAGGCUUCCAGGCCAGAAGCCUUUUAAAAGGUCCCUGCGAGGUUCAGAUGCUUUGAGUGAGACCAGCUCAGUCAGUCAUAUUGAAGACUUAGAAAAGGUGGAGCGCCUAUCCAGUGGGCCGGAGCAGAUCACCCUCGAGGCCAGCAGCACUGAGGGACACCCAGGGGCUCCCAGCCCUCAGCACACCGACCAGACCGAGGCCUUCCAGAAAGGGGUCCCACACCCAGAAGAUGACCACUCACAGGUAGAAGGACCGGAGAGCUUAAGAUGAGACUCAUUGUGUGGUUUGAGACUGUACUGAGUAUUGUUUCAGGGAAGAUGAAGUUCUAUUGGAAAUGUGAACUGUGCCACAUACUAAUAUAAAUUACUGUUGUUUGUGCUUCACUGGGAUUUUGGCACAAAUAUGUGCCUGAAAGGUAGGCUUUCUAGGAGGGGAGUCAGCUUGUCUAACUUCAUGUACAUGUAGAACCACAUGUUUGCUGUCCUACUACGACUUUUCCCUAAGUUACCAUAAACACAUUUUAUUCACAAAAAACACUUCGAAUUUCAAGUGUCUACCAGUAGCACCCUUGCUCUUUCUAAACAUAAGCCUAAGUAUAUGAGGUUGCCCGUGGCAACUUUUUGGUAAAACAGCUUUUCAUUAGCACUCUCCAGGUUCUCUGCAACACUUCACAGAGGCGAGACUGGCUGUAUCCUUUGCUGUCGGUCUUUAGUACGAUCAAGUUGCAAUAUACAGUGGGACUGCUAGACUUGAAGGAGAGCAGUGAUUGUGGGAUUGUAAAUAAGAGCAUCAGAAGCCCUCCCCAGCUACUGCUCUUCGUGGAGACUUAGUAAGGACUGUGUCUACUUGAGCUGUGGCAAGGCUGCUGUCUGGGACUGUCCUCUGCCACAAGGCCAUUUCUCCCAUUAUAUACCGUUUGUAAAGAGAAACUGUAAAGUCUCCUCCUGACCAUAUAUUUUUAAAUACUGGCAAAGCUUUUAAAAUUGGCACACAAGUACAGACUGUGCUCAUUUCUGUUUAGUAUCUGAAAACCUGAUAGAUGCUACCCUUAAGAGCUUGCUCUUCCGUGUGCUACGUAGCACCCACCUGGUUAAAAUCUGAAAACAAGUACCCCUUUGACCUGUCUCCCACUGAAGCUUCUACUGCCCUGGCAGCUCGCCUGGGCCCAACUCAGAAACAGGAGCCAGCAGAGCACUCUCUCACGCUGAUCCAGCCGGGCACCCUGCUUAAGUCAGUAGAAGCUCGCUGGCACUGCCCGUUCCUACUUUUCCGAAGUACUGCGUCACUUUGUCGUAAGUAAUGGCCCCUGUGCCUUCUUAAUCCAGCAGUCAAGCUUUUGGGAGACCUGAAAAUGGGAAAAUUCACACUGGGUUUCUGGACUGUAGUAUUGGAAGCCUUAGUUAUAGUAUAUUAAGCCUAUAAUUAUACUCUGAUUUGAUGGGAUUUUUGACAUUUACACUUGUCAAAAUGCAGGGGGUUUUUUUUGGUGCAGAUGAUUAAACAGUCUUCCCUAUUUGGUGCAAUGAAGUAUAGCAGAUAAAAUGGGGGAGGGGUAAAUUAUCACCUUCAAGAAAAUUACAUGUUUUUAUAUAUAUUUGGAAUUGUUAAAUUGGUUUUGCUGAAACAUUUCACCCUUGAGAUAUUAUUUGAAUGUUGGUUUCAAUAAAGGUUCUUGAAAUUGUUACCAGUGAAUUCAGUUUAUAAAUCUUAUUACAAAAGACUUACCCACGUACCUGAAAUAGCUGCCGAUAGACCAGUGAGAGGUAGGUUCUCCUCUGCCCGUUAUUACCGACCAAAAAAAAAACUGGACAUCAAUUUUUUAGUAAACCAAAAAAUAAGUCUCAACAAAUGCCUUUGCCAAAAUAAGGUUUUAUUUUGAAAGUCAUUUGAUGAAAGUCAUUUGAAAGACACUGAGGAGGGAAGGAGGCCUAAGACCCAACAGAUGUAGGAUCCAGAUCUGGAUUCGUGCCAGCCCCACCAAUGGUCUGUCAGGCCAAGAAGGUGCUUUCUUUGGUAAUUCAUGUUUUUUAACUUCCUGGAGAAGAGAUCUUUUCCCACAAGCCAUCUUCAUUUUUUUUGUAGAGUAGGGCUUUAUUUCCAGAAAACAGUGUGUGAGCUGGAGAUGGGUGUUUUUUUAAAAACAUCAAGGUAGAUCUAAUAUGUUCAACAAAGUGGGGUGGCUCAGCCAGAGGCGAAGUGGAAAGAUUCUGAAAACACAAGAUGGUGGGCAUUAGAGAAGCCAACCUUACUGUCCCCUGCUGUGAUAAAGAUGUCAAAGUAUCUUUGUUCUUGGACACAAAUAUAUAUAAUAAAAUACGUUAAGAAAUGA